CUCUUCCCCGCGGAGCCCGCGCAGUCCGCGCAGCCCUCAUCGCAACUGGGCCCGCGCGCAGAUCCACCAAAGAGAAAGCAGCCCUGUGCCAGUUGCUCUGCCAGCCUUUCACAGGAGAAGUGUCACUAGAAUACUACAGCCCCCACAGGCUCUGCUCCACAGAAACUUAAGGCUGAAAGAGUGUCCGCCAUCAGGGACAUCCUCUGUCACUACGGCCUUACAUAGGAAGUCCUUCUAAAGAGCUGCCUGCCAGCUGCCCUUCCCCAGAUCCCGAAUAUCCUCCUGGCCAGGUGGAGCAGAGAACAGUUCCUCAGCUGGUCAUGCUGAGCUCAUACCCUGAUGGCUGCUCCAUGAGGUCAAGACUGGGUCUCCUCCCUCCUCCCCCUUCACCAAUGCCUGGUCUCACGGGGCUAGUUUUGACCCCCACGCUAUGGCAUCAUCGACCUCCCUCCCAGCUCCUGGCUCUCGGCCUAAGAAGCCUCUAGGCAAGAUGGCUGACUGGUUCAGGCAGACCCUGCUGAAGAAGCCCAAGAAGAGGCCCAACUCCCCAGAAAGCACCUCCAGCGAUGCUUCACAGCCUACCUCACAGGACAGCCCACUACCCCCAAGCCUCAGCUCAGUCACGUCUCCCAGCCUGCCACCCACACAUGCGAGUGACAGUGGCAGUAGUCGCUGGAGCAAAGACUAUGACGUCUGCGUGUGCCACAGUGAGGAAGACCUGGUGGCCGCCCAGGACCUGGUCUCCUACUUGGAAGGCAGCACUGCCAGCCUGCGCUGCUUCCUGCAACUCCGGGAUGCAACCCCAGGCGGCGCUAUAGUGUCCGAGCUGUGCCAGGCACUGAGCAGUAGUCACUGCCGGGUGCUGCUCAUCACGCCGGGCUUCCUUCAGGACCCCUGGUGCAAGUACCAGAUGCUGCAGGCCCUGACCGAGGCUCCAGGGGCCGAGGGCUGCACCAUCCCCCUGCUGUCGGGCCUCAGCAGAGCUGCCUACCCACCUGAGCUCCGAUUCAUGUACUACGUCGAUGGCAGGGGCCCUGAUGGUGGCUUUCGUCAAGUCAAAGAAGCUGUCAUGCGUUAUCUGCAGACACUCAGUUGACACUUGUUAUAUCAUGGGACCCCGGAAAUUGGAGUGAAGCUAGAAACAGAAAACCCAUGCAGGGCCUCGGAUUCCCACAAAUGUGACAAGAGGUAUAGGGAGUGAGUCACAGCGCUUUGCUCGUGACCCUGGGAUCAGAGCACCCAUCAGGCUUCCAUUACUGUGGGCUCCCUAAGAAGACCAUGGAGAGCUUGGGGACUCCCCCAGGAAGGCCGUGAAGCUGGGGAUUCCCCCUAGGAAAGCCAUGAGGAAGCUGGGGACUCCCCAAGAAGGCCAUGAGGAAGCCAGAAAUUGGAGGUGGUAGGAAGUGGUACUGAUCAAUGAUGGCCAGCAGGACUCAUCUCCUGCCUAACUGGACAGGAAGCCUGGCACCCACUUCUGUCUUCCCCUGGAACUGGGCACUGGCGUACACUGGUAUCCCUCCUAAAGAAGUGACUCACCUGACUGAUCAGCAAGAAGCCUAGAUUGCAGGCCUCACCAUGGAUGGUCUUCCUAGUUGCCUGGGGAAACCCUGGAAUGGGCAUCAGGAGAAAGCAACAAGAAUCCAGUCCUUCACACUCACACUACUCUGUUCCUCUUCCCAGAGACAUCGAUUCACUUCAAAGAGCUGUAGGGAAGAUGCAGUCAGCACUGCACUGUAUUUUUUAUUUAUUGCCUAGGUGCCAUUAAAGACACAAACCUAGAAGCCUAGAGGCCAUUCUGAAUAUGGGGGUGGGGUGGUGGAGGGAGCAAGUGAAGAGAUGGGAAUCCAGGGCUCAGGGUUCAAUGCCUUCACCUGAGAUCACAAGCCCAUGGAUGCUGUGACAUCUGGGAGCUUCAUCAGUGGUCUGGCUAAAGCUGAUACUUUCACAGUCACCAUCUUCACCUUUGGACUGGGAAGAAUCACCAUUUUUCUUCUGGCAGAUGACUGUAUUCCUUAUAGGACAGGCAAGGUUUCAUUCAUCUGUUCUCAGUAAGUUUGUUGUUGAACUGAAAUGAAUUUCAUUAUUUCCUCCAAUGUGUACUUUUGUGCCCCCCUCUCACUUCUCCCUAUCAUGACCCCUCUUUUGCUGAAAAAAAUUUUUAUUAUUUUUUCUAUCUCUAGUUCUAGAAAGAGAAAAUUUAUUUUUUAAAUUAUAAACUAUUUUGCCAGGCGCCAUGGCUCACACCUGUAAUCUCAGCACUUUGGGAGGCCGAGGCAGGUGGAUCACCUGAGGUCAGGAGUUCAAGACUAGCCUGGCCAAUAUGGUGAAACCCUGUCUCUACU